AGGUGGACAACAGCAACUUCUCAGAACUACUCUUCACUCCUAACUUCUCCCGAGCCUCUAGAAGAGAAACGCACUCUUCUGGGUCCUAACGGAGUCUGGAAGAAGGCUUUGGACAGAACAGGGACUAGGUUUUGUGGACAGAAACAAAGUGUUUGGGAGAGAUUAUGGCCAGUGGUCAAGCGCGCCCCCCGUUUGAGGAGGAGAGCCCCCAGCCUAGCACAACGGUACGGUCCCCCGAGGUGGUGGUGGAUGAUGAAGUGCCAGGACCAUCAGCCCCUUGGAUAGAUCCCAGCCCCCAGCCUCAAUCCCUUGGCCUGAAAAGGAAGAGCGAAUGGUCAGACGAAUCCGAGGAGGAGCUGGAGGAGGAGCUGGAGUUGGAGCGCGCCCCUGAGCCCGAGGACACCUGGGUGGUGGAGACGCUGUGUGGGCUCAAGAUGAAGCUGAAGCGAAAGCGAGCAUCCUCCGUGCUCCCUGAGCACCACGAGGCCUUCAACAGGCUCCUUGGGGAUCCUGUCGUUCAAAAAUUCCUGGCCUGGGACAAAGACCUGAGGGUGUCAGACAAGUAUCUCCUGGCUAUGGUCAUAGCGUAUUUUAGCCGUGCCGGCCUCUUCUCGUGGCAAUACCAACGCAUUCAUUUCUUCCUGGCUCUCUACCUGGCCAGUGACAUGGAGGAGGACAACCAGGCCCCGAAACAAGACAUCUUCUCCUUCCUCUACGGGAAGAACUACUCCCAGCGACCCUUGUUCCAUAAGCUUCGAUACCAGCUCCUCUGUUCCAUGCGCUGGAGGACGUGGGUUUCCCCAGAGGAGAUGGAGGAGAUCCAGGCUUAUGACCCAGAGCACUGGGUGUGGGCCCGAGAUCGCACCCUCAUUUCCUAGAGCUCCGGGGACAUGGAGGCCUGAGGUCAUCGGCCUGAGGGAAGAACACUGGGCCCAGGGGAGAUGGGAAUUUUCAGCAGGAAGUUUAUCGCGACGCUAAUGCCAGACACCAGGAAGGGAGAGAGGAGCCUCCUGUGCAGAUCAUCUAGAAGAAGCUGGACUCUUCUAGAAGGGGCAAAAUAGAUUGACCAGGUUUUCCUCCUAGGAGCCAUGGAGGUAUUUCUAGGAGUCAGUGGAGGGAAAGUGAGAAACCAGGGGUGUUUCUGGUUCCACCCCUUCCUGCGGCAAAACCUCCCUUUUCACGUUGCUGAAUCCCAGCCUCCCCUGGGCUGGAAGCUGGAGUUCCUGUUUCCUAUGGACUUGGUUGCCACAGUCCAGAGCAUUUGAAGGCACAGCGCAGGCACUCAGAUUGUUACGGAAUUCUUUGUAAAAUAUGAAAUUACUGCCAUAGGAUUUUAAGAGAUAGUUUAAUAGAUACUGUACAUUUUGUUGGUUUAUUUUUCAAAUGUUGGCCAUAGAAUUAUUACUAGGUUGAUUUAAAAUAGUUUGGGGUUUUUGUAGUUUUGAAAACAUGCUGUUCCUAUAGAGUUCUCUGACGGUUGUUAUAUACACAUAAAUAUAAUUUAGUUUUCAUUUUUAAGAGAGGAUUCUUUUUAUCGUAAAUGUUUUCUCUUUAAAUCGUUUUAUCUAUUAUUAAAUGUGCUCCUGAAGCGAGCACUCUUGUAAUCUAUGAUACUGACCUAAUAUAUCCAUUAUAUUUAUAGCUAGGUGGUAGUUCCCCUACAUUCUUGCAAAUAGAAAUGUUUAUUUUCUGUUUACUGUUUGUUACUGAAUUGUGAGAAUUCAGUUGUGAUUUUUAACAUGCCUUCCAUAUAUACUAACAUGUCCAAUAUAUACUAUACAUUUUAUUUGUUUAUUUUGAAAAUGAUGGGCAUGGCAUUAUUACUACAUUUAUUUAACUAGUUUAGAAAUACAAGUAUUUUUUAAAAGACACUGUUCUUAUGAAGUUGUGUGAUGGGUGUUACACCUGUUAUAUACACAUAGAUAUAAUUCUGUUUUCAUUUUUAAGAGAGGAUUCUUUUUAUCCUAAAUGUUUUAUUUUUAAAUCUUUUUAUCUGUUAUUACAUGUGCUGCUGAAGGGAGCACUGUUAUGACCUAGAGUAGUUACAUAAUAUAUCUAUUCUAUUUAUAGCUAGGUGGCAUUUCCCCGAAAUUCUUGUAAAAAUAAAUUUUUAUUUGAUGUUGAGUGUUUGUUUGUUAUUGAACUGUGAGAAUUCAGACGUAAUUUUUUAGCUUGUAUUGAAAGGUUUGUAUGUUACUUUAAAGAGGACAUGUGUUUGAAAGGAGGACAGGAGCUGUGUGUUUCAAAGAGGACAGUGCACUGCGCUACCUGGGAAAAUGCAAUAAAGAUGAAGUUUUCUCAUCUUCA